AGUCAAUCCAGAGCCUCAGCAAGCAGCAGCUGGAAACGGGGAAGAGGGAGCAGACAGGAAGCGGGAGGUCAGCUGUACACCCAGGGUAAUAGAACUUCUACCCUCAGAGGAGUCAAAGAGGAGGCAGAACUAUGGCAGGAAAGCUCCGGAAGUCCCACAUCCCUGGAGUGAGCAUCUGGCAGCUGGUGGAGGAGAUCCCUGAAGGCUGCAGCACGCCGGACUUUGAGCAGAAGCCCGUCACCUCGGCUCUGCCAGAGGGGAAAAAUGCUGUCUUUCGGGCUGUGGUCUGUGGGGAGCCCAGGCCCGAGGUGCGUUGGCAGAACUCCAAAGGUGACCUCAGUGAUUCCAGCAAGUACAAGAUCUCCUCCAGCCCUGGCAGCAAGGAGCACGUGCUGCAGAUCAACAAGCUGACAGGCGAGGACACGGAUCUGUACCGCUGCACAGCAGUAAAUGCGUACGGAGAGGCCGCUUGCUCAGUGAGACUCACUGUCAUCGAAGUUGGCUUUCGGAAGAAUCGGAAGAGGCACAGGGAACCGCAGGAAGACCUCAGGAAGGAGCUGAUGGACUUCCGGAAGUUGCUGAAAAAGAGGGCCCCACCAGCCCCCAAGAAAAAGAUGGACCUUGAGCAGAUAUGGCAGCUGCUGAUGACAGCAGACAGGAAGGACUACGAGAAGAUCUGCUUGAAGUAUGGCAUCGUCGACUACCGUGGCAUGUUGCGCAGGCUGCAGGAGAUGAAGAAGGAACAGGAGGACAAGAUGGCACAGUACAUCAACACCAUCUCCAGCUUAAGACACAUCAGGGUCACCAAGGAUGGGAAUGCAAAGUUUGACUUGGAGCUGGAUCUCAAGGAUUCUCAGAGCAAGAUUUACCUGUAUAAGGAUGGUGAGAUGAUCCCCUAUGGCUUCAACAACCAAACCAAGCACUGUCUGCGCCGGCUGGGGAAGCGCUAUGAGUUCCAGAUUCAAGACCUGAGGCCUGAGGACUCUGGCAUUUACCAGGUCAAGGUGGAGGAUGCUGUGGUCUUCUCCACAGAACUGGAGGCCAGUGCCAUCCCCCCAAGAGUGGUGGUCCCACUGGCGGAGACCCACUGUGAGGAGCAGGGUGACGCAGUCUUUGAAUGUACCCUCUCCAGCCCCUGCCCUAGUGCAGCCUGGCAUUUCCGGCACCGGCUACUCCACCCCAGUGACAAAUAUGAAGUGUAUGUGUCCCCUGACGGGCUGACCCACCGGCUGGUGGUGAGGGGGGCACGUUUCUCAGACAUGGGCCCCUAUUCGCUGGGCACCGGGCUCUACACUUCCAGCGCCUGGCUGGUGGUUGAAGCUGGGAAGGAUAAAGACCUUCAGUCCACAAGUGCUGACCACAAACUGCAGAGGCAAGGAGCCCAGGCAUCAGGAGCAGAAGAGUCUGGGAGCAUCGAGAGCCAGGGAGAGAAAUCCAGAGAGCAGGGCCCCAGGGGGGGCUCCCUUGAAGGGGCUGGGCCGGCUUCUGGGCUCCAGCACAUAGCCAGCCCAGACAGGGAUGGCCUUGGCAGACAUGGCUACUCCUUGAUGGGGGACAAAGGGACAGCUGACUCAGCCUGGGGCCCUGGACAGGAGGGCGAGGGCUUUCCAGUAGCAGAGGGAAGCAGAGCCACUCUUCCCAGGGAAAAUCAAUCCCACAGAGAGGGAGGCUGGGCCAGAAGCCUUGCAGAGAGGCCCCAUCUACAGGGAGAGAGCUCAGAAUCAGGGUUGGGCCUCCCAGAAAAACAACAGCAAGAUCGUGGCAGAGACAGCAACAGUGAUGAAUGCUGGAGGAAAGCAGGAGGCUGGGAGGCUGGGUCCAGUCGGCUUCAGGCUGGAGGACUGGGGAGCAGCAGGGAAGGAAAGGAGCACAGAGGGGACAGUGGAAGACAACUGGACAGGCAUGCCCCAGAGCAACUGUGGGAUGCUCGACUGGGACCUGGGAGAGGAAAGAGCGACCUGCAGGGAUGCCAGUCUGAUCCUGUAGGGUCCUGGCCAAGAGGAAAGCAGAUAGAGAUUUCACAGGAUGACAGCCUGGCUGAGAUGGACAGAGGGGAUGCUCCAAGUAGGGAAAGGGGGAGAGGAAUAGUAGUGUGGGGUGGUGGGACUGGCCUGGGAGAAGCUGGAGACAGCAAUGGGGCAGGAGGUCCUGGCACCCUGGAGCUUACUGGAGGAAGAGGUUCUGGCUCCAAGGUGGGCAUGGCCCCUGAAUCCUGGGGUUCUCAGGGAGGUAGAGAUGCUGACUAUGGGGAAGCCAGGGGCUACUGGGGGUCAGGAGAGUUGCUAGAACAGAUACCUGGAGGCAAGGACUUCCAGGAACCAUCAAUAUCAGGUGGUAGAAAAUUCCUUCUGGGAGAUGGGAGUCCUGAGAUCAAAGCUGAAGACUCACUGCAGGAGGCAGAUGGUAUAUGCCGGGGGGAGUCUGUAGUUACAGGAAGUGCCUACAAAACUGGCCCUGGAGGCCCAGGAGACCCCAGAGGCUGCGAAGGUGUCCUACAGGAGCUCAGGGGAAGGGAUGGCCAGGAAACAGCUUGGGCCUCGGGUGAGGUAGAGUAUGACCCCAGAAGCUUCCAGUCUUCCCAGGGCUGGACAGCAGGUCACAGAGCAGCAGGGGGUAUUGGCAGAAUAGAAUCUAAGGGCACAAGUCCUUGGGAUGACACACCAUCUAGCCUCAGAAAAACUGGGGCCCACCAUGGGCCUGGAGUGCUGGGGCCCAGUGGAGGACAAGAGGGUAUGGGUGGUAUCUGGGUGGCUGGACUGACGGAGUCUGGUCAGGGGGUGGAUGCCAGAAGCCACUGGCUAAGUAGGGCUCCAGGCCUGGGUGCUCAGGGAUCUGGGGGGACACUAGGAGAUAAGAAAGGAUUAAGAGGUCCUGGGUCAAUAGGGUCUGAACCAGAUUUCUGGAAUGGGUCAGGGAGCUCCAGAGUAAAAGGACCCAGAGGUGAGACAGGCUAUAAGGAUGGCUUGGAAGGUCCCGGGAGAAUGGAAUCUAGGUACGAGGGUGGCUUAGGAUAUUCUAGGGAAAUAAGCUCUAAAAGCGGGGCUGGUUAUAGCUAUGGCUCAGGGGUUCCAGGAGAAAUGGGGUCCGGCCAUGGUGCUGGUUGUAGAGUUUCCCCUAGGGCACCUGCGGGAGUGGAGUCUGAGGAAGGGGGUGGGUACAGGCAUGGCUCCGGAGCGCCUGGGGGAGUGUGGUCUGGAAAUGAAGAUUCUGGCCCUGCAGGAGGAGGGUCUGGGAGAGUUGCCAGUCUUAAAAAUGGCUCAGGUGGUCCUGAUGGAGCACCCAUGAAUGACACCAGGAAUUGGGCCUCUGCAUGCCAGGCAGGCAUGGACCCUAGGGGAGGGCACCAUUCAGAUGGUGGCCUAGGGAGUCCUGGGGUGACAGGGUCUGCGGGUAGAGGUGGUCUCAAGGCCCCUGGAGUAGUGGAGACUGUUGGGAUGGGAUGUGUGGAAGCAGAACCAGAGAGCUCUGGAAGAAUAAGGCCUUGGGGUCAGACUGGAAAUUAUGGGGGCUUCAGAGCCUCAGAGGCCCUGGGGGCCUUUGGAGAAGGAGGCUAUGAAGAUGGCUCUGGGGGUCCAGGAGCCAUGGGACCAGGGUCUCUGAGGGCAGGAAGCAAAGUGGGUGAGGGGGAUGGGACAAGAUGCCCUGGUGCUAAGGCCUCUGGAGCUGGAGCUGGUUAUAGGGAUGAUACCAGGCACCCUGAGUCACUCGCACCUCACAAUGGGGCCGCUUCUGGGAGCCAGUGGGCUUAUGGGGCUGGCAAUGUGCUGGGUUAUGAGGAUGGAUCAGAACUUCCAGGGCCUCAGGGAACUGGGGUCAGAACAGCCUAUGGAGAAAGGUCAAGGGGCCUUGGGCCUAGGAGUACAGGGCCAGGGGGUGAGGCAGGCUUUAGAGAUGGUUCAGGAGGCCUCCAAGGAAUGGGAUCAGCAGAUGGGCCAGGUUGUAGGAAGGGUAUUGGGAGUUCUGGGGAAAUGGGGUCAGUGGAUAAGGAAGGUUAUAAGAAAGAUUUGGGGGCUCCUGAGAAUAUGGGUUCGGGGAGCAAGGCAGAUUAUAGGGAUGGUGUAGGGGGUUCUGGGGCAAUGGGGUCAAUGGAUGAAGCAGGUUAUAGGAAAGAUUUAGGGGCUCCUGAGGGAAUAAGUUCAGGGAGCAAGGCAGAUUAUAGGGGUGGUUUACAGGAUUCCAGGGAAGCGGGUUCAGGGAGCAAGGCAGAUUAUAGCGGUGGUUUAAAGGGUUCCAGGGAAAUCGGGUCAAUGGAUGAAACAGAUAAUAGGAAAGAUUUGGGGGUUCCUGAGGGAAUGGGUGCAGGUUACAGGGCUGGUUUAAGGGGUCCUGGGGAGAUGGGGUCACUGGAUGAGUCAGGUCAUAGGAAUGGGAUUGGAGGUUAUGGGGAAAUGGGGUCAGGUUAUAGGGAGGAUUUGGGGGCUCCUGAGGGAAUGGGCACAGGGAGCAAGGCAGGUUAUAGGGAUGGCUUAAGGGGUUCUGGAGAAAUGAGGUCAAUGGAUGAGGCAGGUUAUAGGAAAAAUUUGGGAGCUCCUGAGAGAAUGGAUUCAGGGAGCAAGGCAGGUUACAGGGGUGGUUUAAGGGGUUCUGGGGAAAUGGGGUUAAUUGAGGCAGGCUAUAGGAAAGAUUUGGGGGUUUCUGAGGGAGGGGGUUCAGGGAGCAAAGCAGGUUAUAGGGGUGGCUUAGGUUCUGGGGAAAUGGGGUCUGUGGAUAAGGCAGGCUAUAGGAAGGAUUUGGGGGCUUCUGAGGCAAUAGGUUCAGGGAGUAAGGCAGGUUUUACGGAUGGUUUAGGAGGUUCUGAAGAAAUGGGGUCAGUGAAUAAGGCAGGUUAUAGGAAGGAUUUGGGGGCUCCUAAGGGAAUGGGUUCAGGGAGUAAGGCAAGUUUUAGGGAUGGUUUAGGAGGUUCUGGAGAAAUGGGGUCAGUGAAUGAAGCAGGUUAUAGGAAGGACUUGGGGGUUCCUGAGGGAAUAGGUUCAGGAAGUAAGGCAGGUUUUAGGGAUGGUUUAGGGGGUUCUGAAGAAAUGGGGUCAGUGAAUAAGGCAGGUUAUAGGAAGGAUUUGGGGGCUCCUAAGGGAAUAGGUUCAGGGAGCAAGGCAGGUUUUAGGGAUGGUUUAGGGAGUUCUGGGGAAAUGGGGUCAAUGGAUGAGGCAGGUUAUAGGAAGAAUUUGGGGGCUCCUGAGGGAAUAGGUUCAGGGAGUAAGGCAGGUUUUAGGGAUGGUUUAGGGAGUUCUGUAGAAAUGGGGUCAGUGAAUGAGGCAGGUUAUAGGAAGGAUUUGGGGGCUCCUGAGGGAAUGGGUUCAGGGAGUAAGGCAGGUUUCAGGGAUGGUUUAGGGGGUUCUGGAGAAAUGGGGUCAGUGAAUGAAGCAGGUUAUAGGAAGGAUUUGGGUGCUCCUAAGGGAAUAGGUUCAGGGAGCAAGGCAGAUUUUAGGGAUGCUUUAGGGAGUUCUGGGGAAAUGGGGUCAAUGGAUGAGGCAGGUUAUAGGAAGGAUUUGUGGGCUCCUGAGGGAAUAGGUUCAGGAAGUAAGGCAGGUUUUAGGGAUGGUUUAGGGAGUUCUGUAGAAAUGGGGUCAGUGAAUGAGGCAGGUUAUAGGAAGGAUUUGGGGGCUCCUGAGGGAAUGGGUUCAGGGAGUAAGGCAGGUUUCAGGGAUGGUUUAGGGGGUUCUGGAGAAAUGGGGUCAGUGAAUGAAGCAGGUUAUAGGAAGGAUUUGGGUGCUCCUAAGGGAAUAGGUUCAGGGAGCAAGGCAGAUUUUAGGGAUGCUUUAGGGAGUUCUGGGGAAAUGGGGUCAAUGGAUGAGGCAGGUUAUAGGAAGGAUUUGUGGGCUCCUGAGGGAAUAGGUUCAGGAAGUAAGGCAGGUUUUAGGGAUGGUUUAGGGAGUUCUGUAGAAAUGGGGUCAGUGAAUGAGGCAGGUUAUAGGAAGGAUUUGGGGGCUCCUGAGGGAAUGGGUUCAGGGAGUAAGGAAGGUUUCAGGGAUGGUUUAGGGGGUUCUGAAGAAAUGGGGUCAGUGAAUAAGGCAGGUUAUAGGAAGGAUUUGGGGGCUCCUAAGGGAAUGGGUUCAGGGAGUAAGGAAGGUUUCAGGGAUGGUUUAGGGGGUUCUGAGGAAAUGGGGUCAAUGGAUGAGGCAGGUUAUAGGAAGGAUUUGGGGGCUCCUGAGGGAAUAGGUUCAGGGAGUAAGGCAGGUUUCAGGGAUGGUUUAGGGGGUUCUGAAGAAAUGCGGUCAAUGGAUGAGGCAGGUUAUAGGAAGGAUUUGGGGGCUCCUGAGAGAAUAGGUUCAGGAAGUAAGGCAGGUUUUAGGGAUGGUUUAGGGAGUUCUGUAGAAAUGGGGUCAGUGAAUGAGGCAGGUUAUAGGAAGGAUUUAGGGGCUCCUAAGGGAAUGGGUUCAGGGAGUAAGACAGGUUUCAGGGAUGGUUUAGGGGGUUCUGAAGAAAUGGAGUCAAUGGAUGAGGCAGGUUAUAGGAAGGAUUUGGGGGCUCCUGAGGGAAUAGGUUCAGGAAGUAAGGCAGGUUUUAGGGAUGGUUUAGGGAGUUCUACAGAAAUGGGGUCAGUGAAUGAGGCAGGUUAUAGGAAGGAUUUGGGGGCUCCUAAGGGAAUGGGUUCAGAGAGUAAGGCAGGUUUUAGGGAUGGUUUAGGGAGUUCUGGGGAAAUGGGGUCAAUGGAUGAGGCAGGUUAUAGGAAGGAUUUGGGAGCUCCUGAGGGAAUGGGUUCAGGGAGUAAGGCAGGUUUCAGGGAUGGUUUAGGGGGUUCUGAAGAAAUGGGGUCAGUGAAUAAGGCAGGUUAUAGGAAGGAUUUGGGGGCUCCUAAGGGAAUGGGUUCAGGGAGUAAGGCAGGUUUCAGGGAUGGUUUAGGGAGUUCUGGGGAAAUGGGGUCAAUGGAUGAGGCAGAUUAUAGGAAGGAUUUGGGAGCUCCUGAGGAAAUGGGUUCAGGCAGUUACACAGAUUACAGGAAUGGUUUAGGCAGUUCUGGAAAAAUCAGUUCAGGGGAUGAGGCAGGUUAUAAGAAUGUUUUAGGGGGUUCUGGGAGGAAUCCAUUAGGGAGCGAGGCAGGUUCUAGGGGUAGUUUGGAGGAUUCUGGGUACAUUUUGUCAUGGAAUGAGGCAGGUUCUAGGCAAGGCUUUGGGGGAACUAGUGGCAUGGGGUCAGGGAGUGAGGUCAGUUAUAGAGGAGGCUCAGGAGGAUCUGGGGAAACGGGACCAGAGGGUAAGAUGGGUUAUGGAGAUGGUUCAGGGAGGCUUGGAGUACCAGGCUCACUGGCUGGAAUAGGACAUGAGGCUGGACCCAGAGGCCAUAAAGCCAUGGGUCACAGGUCAGGAUAUUGGGUAGCAUCAGAGGGUGACACGAACUCCAAGGAUGGUCCAGAGCGAGCCAGGGAAACCAGGCUUGUGGAUGGGGCAGGACCUGGGGUGGAACCUGGGAUGGCUGGAAUGCCAGGCACUGCAGGUGGCAUGGCACACAGAGACAGCCUCAGGGGCACAGGGGUGCUGGGGUCUCAGGGAGGGCGACAGACUCUUUCAGAUGAGCGAGGCUCCACCAAAGAUCUUGGGGGCUAUGGAACUUCAGGGAUCCCUGAGGCCUCGGAGGCUGCUGGUGCCAAGGGAAAACCAGAUGUCAAAGAAUGGCAAGACAGUUCUGGGACUCCAGGGUCUUCUAGAGACAGAGGGGCUCCCAGGGUGAAGGAUAGGUCUCCAGACCAAGCAGGGAUAAUGGGGGCUUCUGGGUUUCUUGAUGGCAAGGGGGCAGUGGAAGGUGAGACCUGGGCAGGAAUGGCUGCUCUAGGGUCUGGAUAUGAACGGGACAUCUGGAAAGCAGGCCCAGGAAUGACAGACAGGGGUAGAGUUGCUGGCCAGGGGGGGUUGGCAUCUCAGGGAGGUGGGGACUCACUUUUGGGAGGCAGAAGGGUAGGCUCAGGGAGUUCAGUGGGGACAGGUCAGGAUCUGGACAGCGGCUCUAUGCCUGGGGGAAGGGGCAAGUCAACAUCAGGGCCUGCUGAUAGACAAGGGACGAGCAAUGCUUGGGCUCCUGAUUGGGAAAACCAGGGGUUUAGCCAAGGCAGCAUAGAUGCUGGGAAGCAGCCCGCAGGCUCCAGAGCUUCCGGUUCUCUGCAGGAGAAAGAUGCCGCUUUUGGUGGGACCCAUGAAGGGCCAGGGGGCUUUAAGGGUGGGGAGGGUGCACCAGGCCAAGAGGCGGCUGGUGGAUGCCGAAGCCCAUGGUCCCUGGAUAGCAAAGGUUCAAGUCCUGGAAGGGGCAGUUCUGUUGAUGCAGAGGACUCAGGUAUCCUGGGCAAGGGGAAUUCUACUGAGUGGGGGAAUGCCCUCACCCCAAAACCUGGGGAGUCCGGACCUCAGGGAGCCUGGAAUGGCUUAGAUGGUCCCUUUGGCAGAAAAGCCUCUAGAGAUAGGUCAGGAGGGACCCAGGACCUGAGCUCUCAGCGAGGCAAGGGACAGAGAGGAGGAAAGAGGUCCCUCGGGGAGCAGGGGUCCCUGGAGGCUGAGAAUGGUGAGGUCCAGGGUCCUGGGGCCCUAAAGGAGGAUGAAGGGCAGGGAGUGGAAGAGGCUGGGAGGUCAGGCAGGAGGCCUGGCUCACUCAGGAGCAGGUCUCAGGCACAGUCAGGGGCUGAGGUUGGAGGAGGAAAGAGAAGGGGAGCAGACGAGGCUGGAAGCAUGGGGUGGCAGCCUAUGGGAGAGAACUGGGGGUGCCUGGAGGAGAUGCUGAAUGAAGAUCAGAGCCGGGAGCCCCCUGGUCACCUUGGUAGCAGGAGAAGUGGCAAAGACGGCAGGUUGGACAUCUAUGGAGAGAGGAGAGAUGCUACCCGGAGUUCCACAUCCAGAUACAAGCCUGGCACUGGCAGUUUCUCCAAGGAUGCCCAAGGCCCCAUGGGCCACUUCUCCCAGGGCCUGGCUGACAUGGAAGUGCAGCCGGGGGAGGCCGCCACACUCUCCUGUACCCUCACCAGUGACCUGGGACCUGGCACCUGGUUUAAGGAUGGCGUCAAGCUCACCACCCAGGAUGGAGUCAUCUUUAAGCAAGACGGUCUCGUGCACAGCCUCUUCAUCACGCAUGUGCAGGGGACCCAAGCUGGGAGGUACACCUUUGUAGCUGGUGACCAGCAGAGCGAGGCCACCCUGACCGUCCAGGAUUCCCCUACCAUUGCUCCAGAUGUGACAGAGAAACUGAGAGAGCCACUGGUGGUCAAGGCUGGGAAGCCGGUGAUAGUGAAGAUCCCCUUCCAGAGCCACCUCCCCAUUCAGGCUGCCUGGAGGAAGGACGGGGCUGAGGUGGUGGGCAGCAGUGACAGGGAGGCCCAGGUGGACCUGGGGGAUGGCUACACGCGGCUGUGCCUCCCCAGCGCAGGCAGGAAGGACUGUGGCCAGUACAGCGUGACACUGAGGAGUGAGGGAGGCUCUGUGCAGGCCGAGCUCACUCUGCAAGUCAUAGACAAGCCUGAUCCCCCACAAGGCCCCAUGGAGGUUCAGGAUUGCCAUAGGGCUGGCGUCUGCCUCCGCUGGCGGCCCCCAAGGGACAAUGGGGGCCGGACUGUAGAGUGCUACGUGGUGGAGAGACGGCAGGCUGGCAGGAGCACUUGGCUGAAGGUGGGCGAGGCCCCCGCUGACAGCACCACCUUCACGGAUGCCCAUGUGGAGCCAGGCAGGAAGUAUACCUUCCGAGUGCGGGCUGUGACCUCAGAGGGGGCUGGCGAGGCCCUGGAGUCUGAGGAGAUAUUGGUGGCUCCUGAGGCUCUCCCCAAGGCCCCUUCCGCGCCAGCCAUCCUGUCGGCCUCCAGCCAGGGCAUCACACUGACAUGGACAGCACCUCGGGGCCCCGGCAGCGCCCACAUCCUGGGCUACCUGAUCGAGAGGCGUAAGAAGGGGAGCAACACCUGGACGGCAGUGAACGACCAGCCGGUGCCUGAGAGGAGGUGGACGGUGGCGGACGUGCGGCAGGGCUGUCAGUAUGAGUUCCGGGUCACAGCUGUGGCUCCCUCAGGUCCCGGAGAGCCUGGACCUCCAUCGGAUGCUGUCUUUGCUCGGGACCCCAUGAGACCCCCUGGGCUGGUGAGGAAUCUCCAAGUCACAGACAGAUCGAACACCAGCAUCACUCUGAGCUGGGCUGGGCCAGACACCCAGGAAGGGGAUGAAGCCCAGGGGUAUGUGGUGGAGCUGUGCAGCUCAGACAGUCUCCAGUGGCUCCCGUGCCAUGUGGGCACCGUGCCAGUCACCACCUACACGGCCAAGGGGCUUCGGCCUGGAGAGGGCUACUUCGUGCGGGUGACAGCAGUUAAUGAAGGAGGCCAGAGCCAGCCCAGUGCCCUGGACACAUUAGUGCAAGCCAUGCCUGUUACUGUCUGUCCCAAGUUCCUCGUGGACUCCAGCACCAAGGACUUGCUGACAGUCAAGGUCGGGGACACAGUUCGUGUGCCCGUCUCCUUUGAAGCCAUGCCCAUGCCUGAGGUGACCUGGCUGAAGGAUGGCUUGCCCUUGCCCAAAAGAAGUGUGACUGUCACUAAGGAUGGCCUCACCCAGCUUCUGAUCCCUGUGGCUGGACUCUCAGACAGUGGUCUCUACACUGUGGUGCUGAGGACCCUGCAGGGGAAGGAGGUUGCCCACAGCUUCCGUAUCAGGGUGGCAGCAUGCCCGCAGGCCCCUGGGCCCAUCCACCUGCAGGAGAACGUGCCUGGGACGGUGACGGCCGAGUGGGAACCCUCUCCUGACGAGGCCCAGGAUGUCCCGCUGCACUACGCGGUGUUCACACGCUCCUCAGCGCACGGUCCCUGGCACGAGGCAGCCGACCGCAUCCACACCAACCGCUUCACCCUCCUGGGCAUCCUCCCCGGCCACGAAUACCACUUCAGGGUGGUGGCCAAGAAUGAGCUGGGGGCCAGCAAACCCUCGGACACCAGCCAGCCCUGGUGCAUCCCCCGGCAGCGCGACAGGUUCACAGUGAAGGCUCCGUGCUACCGGGAGCCCGACCUGAGCCAGAAGCCCCGGUUCCUGGUGGGCCUGCGGUCCCACCUGCUGCCCCAGGGCUGCGAGUGCUGCAUGAGCUGUGCCGUGCAGGGCUCGCCCCGGCCCCACGUCACCUGGUUCAAGAAUGACCGCAGCCUGGAAGGAAACCCCGCGGUGUACAGCACUGACCUGCUGGGCGUGUGCUCCCUCACCAUCCCCAGCGUAUCCCCGAAGGACAGCGGGGAGUACAAGGCUGUGGCUGAGAACACGCUGGGCCAGGCAGUCAGCACUGCCACCCUCAUUGUCAUAGAACCCAGCACCUAGCCUCACCUCACCCUGGGAUGGUCCUGGACCCUUGAAGCUUCACUUCCGACACCUGCACUGGCCCGGGAAGCCAAUCCCAAGGAUGGAGGCUGUGCCCAGAGCCCCAGGAAAAUGGGAGUGAGAAGAUGCCUGGCGAGGUUUUGGCCAGGAGGACGUGAAGUCCUUGGGGAAGAAAAACAAGGGAGGAGGGCAUUCCACCUCCUGGCUCCAAGCUAAGUCACUCAACAGAAUGACAGCGAACCUCCUGGACCCUCACCAUAUGGGUUUCUUUCUUCUUCGCUUCAGGAGAUCCAGAGGGCACCUGCCUGCAGGAUGGGCCGGCUCCUUAUUUUCCUGGGCUGAGCCGUUUGGAGGGAGGGUGGGCACAGCUGGGCCUGCUGUGACCACUGGGAGGGAAGAGGAGAGGAGGUCAGAGGACCUGGGUGAGGACUAGGGCAUCAAGGUCGUGUGUGUGGGUGGGGGCAGCCUCCACCUCCUGGAUUCAAGAGAUUCCAGGGGUGCAGCAAGUGCUUUCUAUGCGUUUCUUCAUUAAAACAUUAGGCUAAUACAGGCA